GCCGCGUUUUGCCUCCGCAGCAGCUCUGGGCUCUUCUCAGCUGCGCGAGCAGCUGCUCCAAUGCCCCGGAGUGGCCAUGGGCGCCCCGCACUGGUGGGACCAGCUGCAGGCUGGUAGCUCGGAGGUGGACUGGUGCGAGGACAACUACACCAUCGUGCCUGCUAUCGCCGAGUUCUACAACACGAUCAGCAAUGUCUUAUUUUUCAUUUUACCGCCCAUCUGCAUGUGCUUGUUUCGUCAGUAUGCAACAUGCUUCAACAGUGGCAUCUACUUAAUCUGGACUCUUUUGGUUGUAGUGGGAAUUGGAUCCGUCUACUUCCAUGCAACCCUUAGUUUCUUGGGUCAGAUGCUUGAUGAACUUGCAGUCCUUUGGGUUCUGAUGUGUGCUUUGGCCAUGUGGUUCCCCAGAAGGUAUCUACCAAAGAUCUUUCGGAAUGACCGGGGUAGGUUCAAGGUGGUGGUCAGUGUCCUGUCUGCGGUUACGACGUGCCUGGCAUUUGUCAAGCCUGCCAUCAACAACAUCUCUCUGAUGACCCUGGGAGUUCCUUGCACUGCACUGCUCAUCGCAGAGCUAAAGAGGUGUGACAACAUGCGUGUGUUUAAGCUGGGCCUCUUCUCGGGCCUCUGGUGGACCCUGGCCCUGUUCUGCUGGAUCAGUGACCGAGCUUUCUGCGAGCUGCUGUCAUCCUUCAACUUCCCCUACCUGCACUGCAUGUGGCACAUCCUCAUCUGCCUUGCUGCCUACCUGGGCUGUGUAUGCUUUGCCUACUUUGAUGCUGCCUCAGAGAUUCCUGAGCAAGGCCCUGUCAUCAAGUUCUGGCCCAAUGAGAAAUGGGCCUUCAUUGGUGUCCCCUAUGUGUCCCUCCUGUGUGCCAACAAGAAAUCAUCAGUCAAGAUCACGUGAUGGCAAGAUGGUGGCUGGCUUCUCUGCUUAUCGCCCCUCAUGCAGUGGGCUUCCUUUGCUAGGAAGACAGCCAAGGGAGUUCGAAUAGUUGGGGUGUGGGCUAUCUUUUCAAAAAUCUAUUUGCUGGGGCUCUUAAUUUCUUUAGUGUUCUUUGUAUGUAGGGAUUUAAACUUUGUCAUAUGGUACAAAUAUUCCCUGCCCCCCUGCAGUUUCCCAUUUGUCUUUCAGUAUGUUAAUAUUUUUGUGCCAUACUGGUUUUAAACUUUCAUGUUGUCACAUCUGUUAAUCUUUUCUUUAGGAUUUCUGGAUUUUGUGUAAUUUUUAAAAAGGUCCCCUCCUCCUCCCUAAUGUGUCUGUGGACCACCUGGAUUCCACUGUACAAGGGGAAAAGUGUCUAUUCCUUUCCCAAAGAUGGAAAAUGGAGGGCUUAGGGACACUAGAUGCAUCUUUCUCAGCAUCACUUCCAGAUGCAGUGACUUGUUGGGCUGCGUCCUUAAUGGCCAUGGCAGAGCAGUCCCUUGGGGGAUCCAGCCCUGUACAAUGCAUCUCUUCCUGGAGAAAGCUGGCCUGCUCCAGACCCCACCAUUCCCAGGCGCCCUUGGAGUGGACUCUACUGAUGACAGACAGACCCUCUGAGAGACAAGACCCUCUGACUCUGUGAUGGAAGAUGCCAGAGAUUUUCCUUUGGGGUAAUUGUCCUUAAACAAAACCAAACAGAUGAAACACACACAGGACUUGUGGCUAAAAAGGCUAGUUUUUCACUUGCAUUUCUCAACUAACCCAGGUUUUACAUGCAUCUGUGAAUCCUUUUACUACUACCUCUGUGGAGAGAUGGAGAGACUUCAGAUAAACGUGAAGCUAAUGAGUAAAACCCUCUCUGCCAAAACCUACACUCCACUUUAGGCCCUUCUUGAAGAUGAGCACAAUUUUUAAAUACUGAGCACAAUUUUUAAAUACUGACAUCACUUCCUCUUCCCCCUCCCACCCCAGCUCAGCAGCCUCAAAUCUACAGAGAAGAAGAAUUAUGGCAUGAACAUUCCCACAGACCCACCAUCUUUAAGACUUGACCUCUGUAAGUUUACCAAAGGGCUCCUCACAAUUGUGGUGGGGGUUCUGGUUCAAAAUUUGGAGCAAACAUGAAGUUUUUGGAAACGUUUUCUCAUUUGAAGCCUCCAGUAUGCUGUACUAUUCUGGAAAUUACCUUCAAGAGUCUCACUUCUUGUUUCUGUUGUGUUUUCUGUGGGCAUCAUGUUCUUCACGCUUGCAGUAGAAGGUGCUUUCUCGGUUUCCCAGAGUAUCCAACGGCUCACCUUUCUCAAGUGCUGGCAGUAGCUAUGCACUCACGGGCUGGUUUGGGUCGCUGGUGCAGCAGCGCAAAUCUGUUGCCUUCUGAAUUUUUCUCACCUAAUGUGACACUGGCUACAAUGAAUCUUCUCUUCAUCGGGCUGAAUGAAAGAUUCAAGAACCAUCUUCAAGGUGCAUGGUGGGAAUUAUCAACCUCAGGGAUACUCAUUUUAACUCAGGCGUGUCCUGCUUUGUAACAUUCCAUUGUUGGGAGAGGGCAGGACAGGUGUGUUCUUCUGUGGGCAGGAGUCAUGUCACUGUCCUACAUAUGUAAGAGUUGGGAAGGUGACGAUUUUUGACACAUCCAGGAACUCUUACUCUAGUUAGAAUUUGUACCAGAUCCAAGGUGAAAACCCCAAUAAGCAACUGAAUUUAGAGUUUAAAAAUGAAUGACUUUAUGCUACAUCUGUGGUUAUCAAAUUAUAUAGGUUGUUGAGAAGCAGAACGCUGUUUGUAGUAAGAAAUCUUUGUGGAACCCCAGUGUGUGAAGUAAAUUGUAUGUUAUUAAAUUUAUUUAAGGUUAAA